AGACCUGCACCCAGUCACAGCAGCACAGAUGUGCAGGAGGAGACCAUUUCCACGGACCCUCCGACUCCUAGGAGGCAGGUUCCUGGGCGAUGCUGACGCCGAUGCUGUGCGUCCUGAGCCACACUUGGGGAGCUACUGCGCAAGCUCGCACAGCUAGCCGACCGCUGAGCUGGGGCUCAGACCUGGGUCAGUCCUGGUCCACAGGCCAGCCCCUUUCUCACGUCCCCUGGUGAACGGCGGCAUGGUGGCCUCAUGGACACUGAGCAGGGCCCCUAGGGAAGCCUGUAUGGAGGCCACUUCACUUUGAAUGGAUCUGGGAUAGAGGAAGGACGCGAGCUGUGGGAGCCUGGGUCCUGGGCACAGCGGGCAUGUCAUGGCAGGGUUCACCAGCCUCCUUUCAGCAGUUCCCUAGUUCUGCCCCAGCUACCUGUGGUUGGUGGUGGGAGGUUUAUUUGUUAGUUCCUUCAGCAGUGACUCACCACACUUACUGAGAGCUUACCGUGUGCCAGGACUGCCACAGGUAUGGGGAUGCAGAGUGUCCACAGCCCCCCAGAAGAUUGAUGAUAGCACCCUCCAUGUAGGAAGGGCUGUGACUGCAGACAGGGCAUGGGGCGGGGCACCUGUGUUUGCCACAACCUCUAGAGGGUCCCUUCAUAUUCACGUCUGUGCGUGGGGCCCUCCUCCACCCAGAUCUGCUUCCGCAGCACAGCCACACAAGUCUACAGCUGGUGACUGUGGCUGGCAAGCAGGGGAAGGUGGGUGGGGGCGGCAGCCGUGGGCUUUCCACUGGGUCCCAGCAGACCAAGUCCUGGUACAAGGAAGCACGGGCUGGCACUGGCAAACCCUCCUCAGGGAGCAGCAGGCCAGGAACCUGGGCUGGGACUAAUUAUUGCUGAAGAGAGAACAGGGCCAAGUGUCCCUCAUGUCCCCCCAGCAGCCGGGGCAAGCAGAGAAAGAAAUGUCGGAACCGGGGAGAGGCCCCUGCCUCUGCACAGGGCUAAACAUCAUGCCAGCUGGCAAGGGAGAAAUGGGUACAGGGCCCAGGGGCAUUAUCACAGAAGAAGGCAAUGAAAGGUGCGUUGGGGGCUGAGGCAACCCAUUAUAACUGCACACAUCACACACCAGGGAUCCACUAAUUUAGACUACAAUGUGAAUGGUCUUUUGAAACUGAGAUGUGUGGGGGCCCAGAGGGAGGGAUCCACCCAGCUGGGAGGAGGUUAGGGAGGUCUUCCUUAAAAUACUUCCUGUUCCGUCUCAGAGAACCCAUGGACACUGGCCAGGGGAGGGAGAGGAAACACGUCGCAGGUGGAGAGAAUCGCUUGUGUGAGGGCACAGAGCGGGGCAAGAAGACAGUGGUGGGCUUUCCCCAGGAGCUGUUCGGCAGAGGGAAAGUGGAUGCUGAGCUCUUCCUCUUCCCUGGAGCAAGUCCCAUUUCCUCAGAGAACACGGCCCCCUUGGGCCAAAAGGACAUGAAGAAGCUCUUGCUAAUGCCAGCCUGGCUCUCCUCAUCCCGCCCCCUGCACCCCUGCCCUUCUGGCUGCCCUCCCUUCUCCUAGCUCUGUCCCCUCUCACUUCAGGAGUCUCAAGUCCUUCAGACUACUCCAAAGUCGGGGGAUCUCUGGAUGGGUAGGAGGUGAUCUCACCGCCUCCUCUCUUGCCCGGGCUUGUCGAGAUGAACUUCCUGAUGCUGGCGGCGCUGAAGCUGACACUAGCGGGGGCACCUCCCUGACAUGAACGCCCCUCGAGACUGGGCCAGUGCUCCUGAUGCCUGGGCACCUGCGGAAAGGCACCCAGCGUGGCCGCCGUGGCAUGCCUUGAGUGUGUGGGUGGGGACUGUUGCAAACUGACAUUCCAGCUGUCCCAGUCCAUUUUGUGCUGCUCUCACACAACCCCGGAGAGUGGGCGAUUCACAAAGGACAGAAAUGUAUCUUCCCACAGCUCUGGAGCCAGGUGCCAGCAGGUUCUGUGCCUGGUGAUGGCUCCAGUCUCUGCUUUCAUGAUGGUGCCUUGCUGCUGCGUCCUCCAGAAGGGACAAAGGCUGCCGUCCUCACAUGGCUGAAGGUGGAAGGGCAACGAGUGAAUGUACUCCCUCCACACAGCACCUACAUCAGGACACCUGAUUCCAUUCAUGGCCUAAUCCCCUCUUAAGGCCCCACCUCUUAAUGCUAGCACAUUGGCAACACCUGGAUUUUGCGGGGGAAACACGUUCAAACCAUAACACCAUCUAAGGCUGCUUCUGCCUGAGACAAGUGUGCUCAUGUCUGCCUCAGAGACGGGGCCAAAAGCAGCUUGCUCUGCCCUGCCCUGGAAGCAGGACAGAGGAUAGCUGUCAUCUCUCCCUUCCAAUGCCAGCUCAUUGUCUCAAACAAAACUUGGCCCCUUGUGCCCUCUAAGGAGUGGGUUCCUGUGCAGGGGCUCCAAGGUUCUUUGUGAUAAUAGACCAGGGAGGGCAAGUUGGUUCCCUCUCAUGCUUGGCAUCCAGGUGUUUGAGGGUAGCUGCCCAGGGCCCUGUGUUGAGGGCACUAUGGUCAGAGCUGGAGCAAGGGGGGGCUGGGUGCAUGAUGAGUUUGCAUGGCAGCUGGAAGUGUCCCCUCUGAGUGGCUCCCUGGAUAUCCCGGGACCACUGGCCGUGUGCAACCUGAGUCCCGGCAUGAACUCCGCUGGGACCCUCCUUCGUGUUAACGCUUCACUUUUCAAACAGGAAAUAGAAGGAAAACAAAGCUGCUUUCUAACAAACACUUUGAUUUUAAAGCCAGAGUAUGAGUCAGAAACAUCAUCCAUUGCAGCCAGCUUUACAUGGGAAUAGCCCAGUUCUUCAAAAGAAGCAGCUGUCAUUUCAUGGCACCGAGGCAUCGUGUUUCCAGAAGAGCCACAGUCCCUCUUGCAUUAAGAUGGGUUGUGACGGACCUCUUAGAGAAUCCGACAGUUUCGGGUUGGAAAGGGGAUCCCUUUUGUUCUGUCUGGACAGUAAGGCAGUGCAUCAUCUACAGGUGCAUCCGCUGCAUGGCUGCUGGCUUGUGGCCUGACAAAAUGCCCAGCAUUGAACCAGAUGCAUAGGUGUGAACUCUGGAGAAUCCUGUUUUCAGUGGCUGGAAGACGGAGGUGUAGGCACCAGCUCAAACUCUUCACCUCACGCCUUCUAUCCUGCAGACCCCAGCAGGCCACAUGGUGACCUUCUAUGUCCAUCUGGGACAGCAGUCAGCUGCCCCUGCCUCUGCGGGGAGUGAGCAAUGGGCCGCAGGAUCACUUGUCCUGGGCAGCUCUUCUGGGGGUGGCUUUGCAUUGCUGCUGGGAUUUGGGAGUCCAGGGCCUGUGGUCUCCUGGGGGCUGCGUGCAGAGUGUCUUCCCCAGAACCAGAUGGGGAAGGGAGCCGCAGGGAAAGAACGUGACCUUUGGGCUCAAUCCUGGUAUUGAAGCCGUGUUCGUUCUUUUACAUUUUCGUAACGUGCAGCAUUGGGUAAAUGCCUUCUGAGUUUGGUUAGUGCUUGUUAAAUUGGGCGAGAACUUCAUAAGGUUGCAGGAAGUAUUCCGAGAAAUGGUACACGCACAGUACUUAGCGUGGUCACCGCACAUGGCCAGCAUGUACCAAACUGGUCCGAAUUGACUAGAAUGGGGAGGGUGGGAAGCGACAAUCUCUACGUUCUCUUUAACCUGAGGUGUCUGAUGCUACUUGCUGGGCUUCUGGCCUGUGAUGAGUGCUCCCACUCCCUGCUGCCCUGAGACCUGUGUGGCUUUCAGGGUAUUCUUUUUUCUCAGUGCCUUUGUGUGGAGAGCCGCUGUCUCCCUCCAUUCUGUGGGUGAUGCAGGUGGCGCUGCUGUGAGCUGCCCCUGGAGGUCAUGGAUAGGCUGUCAAGGACGGGGCCUGCCAUUCCAGAGCUCCCGCCGCCCUGGGGAAGCGAUGUGGGCAGUAGCUCAGAAUGCAGCUUCUCCCUAGACCCUGGGCCACCGGGGACUUGCGAGAGAAAGAACAGGGACGGGGAAGACUGGAUGGUCCUGAAAGCUGAGAGGGGCCACAGAAGCCCAGAUGACACAGGACUAUGGGAGACAAGUGAGGGCACCAGCUUCCCUGGGUUGAGGGACCGUGAUACCCAGGAGGGCAGAGAGGGAGACAGGGCCCGGCUGGCAACCUCUGAGCAGGUGAGUGGGAGAGAGAGCAGGACAGAGAAGGCAGCUCUGUGUUCUGCUCUGAUCCGUCUGACUCCACACGGAUGUGGAGUUCUCUGAGACUCCUUUCCCUGAAUCUGAGAGCUUACUAACAGAAGGCCGGGCCUCUGAGAUAGAGAUCAGGCAUGUAAUGAAUGAAUGUGAAUCAUGAAUACAGCUGGAGCACCCCUCAUCAGGGUAGCCCACACCUUACAACCGUGGACACAGAGGCCUUGUUGCUUCCCCGAAAGUCUAGUUAAUGCCUAGUUAAUAUCUAAUUAAUGACCAGUUAACGACAACGCUCCUAACUCCAUCAUCCCACCCCCUUUCCCCAAAUUCAGCACAAAUGGCUUCAGUUUGAGUUUCCCAAAGCAUCUCCUCAGGUGUGUGGUUACAGCCCAGCCCUAGGGUCUCUGGGUGCAUCGGCUUCCCCCUCCCAGAUCCAAGUACAACUGAAACCCUAACAGUAGAAAUCAUCAUUGCUGGCCCAGCGCUGCCACCACUGCUUCUGUUCAUAGCCUGUUUUGUUUGUUUUUAGUCCCUUAGGGACUGGCCCUAACAACAAAUGAGGAGAAGCCAAGUUCUCUGCUUUCUGCAGACAGGGCCUCCCCUGGAUGGGAUCUUCCUCUGAGGCGAGCUUCAGAUCUGCUCAAGCUUCCUGCAGUGGGGCCAGGAGGCAGGGCCUGGGCAGGGGAGACCAGAACCUCUCGGUGAUGCCUCCGAAUGGCAGGGCUCAGACACACACACCUGGCUGGGUUUCAGAUCCCUUAGUUUUGGGUGCCCAAGUUCACGGAGGGUGCCGGGGAAUAGAAGCUCUGUCAGUCUCGUCUGGAUCUUGGUCCUCAGCAACUGUCUGGAUCCUGACAGGCCUUGGUCUAGGUCUCUCCAGGCCUUUCCUUCCUGGAGCCACAGUGCUUAGAGACAGGCCACUGGGGUCAGCAUUUGAGCUCAGCUAUGAUCAGAAAAAAGCACCGUUGAGGUUGCAGUGAGCCGAGAUCACGCCACUGCACUCCAGCCUGGGCGACAGAGAGAGACUCCAUCUCAAAACAAAAACAAACAAACAAACAGAAAGCACCGUCGAGAAAUGGCUCCAGCGCUGACUAGCGGCCACCUCAUUUCCCCCCUUGACCACUGGGCCAGUUGGGUGGCUAGGUUGCCUCAUUUUGCAUCCUUCUGUAUCCCCAAAUCUGAAAUAAAAGCUGGAAAAAAA